ACUUCCUCGGCGCCUCCCCGGGGGAGGACGGGCGAACGAGGCGCGGACGGACAGGCGGACAGCAGGGCGGACAGCAGGGAGGACAGCAGGGCGGGCAGGGGGCGGACGGCCACGGCGCGGGGGGCGCUCCCGGCUCCCGCUCCCGCGUCCCCGACCCAUGGCGGGCCCGGCCCCGCCCGCGGCCGACGAGCUCCCGGGCCCGGCCGCCAGGCGCCUCUACUCCAGGAUGGAGGCGUCCUGCCUAGAGCUGGCGCUGGAGGGCGAGCGUCUGUGCAAGGCGGGCGACUUCAAGACAGGCGUGGCCUUCUUUGAGGCUGCUGUGCAGGUGGGCACCGAGGACCUGAAGACACUGAGUGCCAUCUACAGCCAGCUGGGCAACGCCUACUUCUACCUGAAGGAGCACGGCCGGGCGCUGGAAUACCACAAGCAUGACCUCCUGCUGGCGCGGACCAUCGGUGACCGCAUGGGGGAGGCCAAGGCCAGUGGAAACCUGGGAAACACACUCAAGGUCCUGGGGCGCUUCGACGAGGCUGCCGUCUGCUGCCAGCGGCAUCUGAGCAUCGCCCAAGAGCAGGGAGACAAGGUUGGGGAGGCGAGGGCCCUCUACAACAUCGGGAACGUGUACCACGCCAAAGGCAAGCAACUGUCCUGGAACGCCGCAAACGCCACGCAGGACCCCGGGCACCUGCCGCCCGAUGUCCGAGAGACCCUGUGCAAGGCCUCCGAGUUCUACGAGAGGAACCUGUCCCUGGUGAAGGAGCUGGGCGACCGUGCGGCGCAGGGCAGGGCCUACGGCAACCUGGGCAACACCCACUAUUUGUUGGGGAACUUCACAGAGGCCACGACCUUCCACAAGGAGCGCCUGGCCAUUGCUAAGGAGUUUGGAGACAAGGCAGCCGAGAGGAGGGCCUACAGCAACCUGGGGAACGCCCACGUCUUCCUGGGGCGCUUUGACGUGGCCGCCGAGUACUACAAGAAGACGCUGCAACUGUCUCGGCAGCUCAGGGACCAGGCAGUGGAGGCGCAGGCCUGCUACAGUCUGGGCAACACCUACACGCUGCUGCAGGACUACGAGCGCGCGGCCGAGUACCACCUGCGGCACCUGCUCAUUGCCCAGGAGCUGGCCGACAGAGUGGGCGAGGGCCGGGCGUGCUGGAGCCUGGGAAAUGCCUACGUGUCCAUGGGGCGCCCAGCGCAGGCCCUGACCUUCGCCAAGAAGCACCUGCAGAUCUCCCAGGAGAUCGGGGACCGCCAUGGGGAGCUCACGGCCCGCAUGAACGUGGCGCAGCUGCAGCUGGUGCUCGGCCGCCUGACCAGCCCGGCAGCCUCAGAGAAGCCUGACCUGGCCGGCUAUGAGGCCCAGGGGGCCAGACCCAAGAGGACGCAGAGGCUGAGCGCGGAGACCUGGGACCUGCUGAGACUCCCCCUGGAGCGGGAGCAGAAUGGAGACAGCCACCAUUCAGGGGACUGGCGGGGGCCCAGCAGGGACUCGCUACCCCUCCCCGUGAGGAGCAGGAAGUACCAGGAAGGCCCGGACGCUGAGAGGAGGCCCCGGGAGGGCAGCCACUCCCCGCUGGACAGCGCCGACGUCCGGGUGCACGUGCCACGCACGAGCAUCCCGAGGGCCCCGUCUUCGGACGAGGAGUGCUUCUUUGACCUGUUGACCAAGUUCCAGAGCAGCCGCAUGGACGACCAGCGUUGUCCCCUGGACGAUGGCCAGGCCGGGGCUGCCGAGGCCACGGCCGCCCCCACCCUGGAGGACAGGAUCGCCCAGCCCUCGAUGACGGCCUCGCCCCAGACCGAGGAAUUCUUCGACCUCAUCGCCAGCUCCCAGAGCCGCCGGCUGGACGACCAGCGGGCCAGCGUGGGCAGCCUGCCGGGGCUGCGAAUCACCCACAGCAAUGCAGGGCACCUCCGAGGCCACGGCGAGCCCCAGGAGCCGGGGGACGACUUCUUCAACAUGCUCAUCAAGUACCAGUCCUCCAGGAUCGAUGACCAGCGCUGCCCGCCACCUGACGUACUGCCCCGGGGCCCUACCAUGCCGGACGAGGACUUCUUCAGCCUCAUUCAGAGGGUGCAGGCUAAGCGCAUGGACGAGCAGCGGGUGGACCUCGCCGGGGGCCCGGAGCAGGGGGCAGGCGGCCCGCCCGAGCCCCAGCAGCAGUGCCAGCCUGGUGCGAGCUAAGGCCCUGUGCCCACCGCCAGGCCCACCCUGCCCCCACUCCUGGACGCCGGUCUCACAGUCACAGCCACGUCCUCCCGAGGCCAUUGCCGAGGACAGGCACUGGGCAUGCAGCCCCACGGCCUCCCCGACCCAGGGCGACAGGCUCAGGCCAAGCUGCCCGUGGUGGGAGGGCGUGCUUCCAUCCCGGGCUGGCCCCCAUGGCCCUCAGCUUCCUCCCUUCUGCCCCUGCCGCAGGCCGGACGGGGCCUUCGGCAUGUCGGCCCCGACCUGGUGCUGUCAGACUCCCGCAUCCUCUCCCCCAAGCCCUUCCCGUUCUGCCCUGCCCUGCCAAAUGUGAAACCCUGCUGUCUCCCCCACCCUCCCCAAAGGUGUCUCUGAGCCGCCUCUUGGGGCCACCAAGGACAGGGCCAUGUUCUGUCCCCCCAGAGCUGGUCUUGGGAUGGCCGUGUGACAGGCAUGCUCCACCCCUCCAGCUUCGUCCUGGGGCAGGGCUCCCUCCAAGCCUGUCUCCCCACUCCCCGGCCAGAGGUCAGCAACCACAGAAGGCCCCCCAGACCACGCAUGGCAGACCAGGCUGCAGUGGCAGCCCUGAGGUGCCCCCCGCCGAGUCCCAGGGCCCUGCAGGGGCCUCGACAGGAGCCGGGCCUAUCUCUAAAGCAGAGGGAAUGGCUGGGCAUGAACUUCGACAUUCCAAAACCCCAAGCCAGGAAAAAGGGCAGGGCCUGGUCCUAGGGAUGCUUACUGGCAGCAAGAGCAGUGCCCAGUCAGGGUGGGAGGUAGCACCAGGCUCUGUGACCCUCACCCAAGUGGGGGGGUGGUCAGUGGAAGCUGGGGAGGCUUCACUCAGCUCAACCCUGCAGACCCCCCAUAUGAGAACCCCCCUCCUCCCACCAGCUGGGGGAGAUGACAUCACUGCUCUCUCCAUGGGGAGGGGGCUCACAGGGCACCAAGUUCGGGAUCCUAGGACUGGCAGGACCUGCUGGAGCCUGAGAUGGGCCCCAGGGGCCUGAGGUUGCCUCCUCCUGUCCAGACCCAGCCUUGGCACCUCCCAAGACUGCCAAGGGCCCUACCAUGGCCCCACAGCCCCCAGGGCUGGCAGUUCCAUCUAGGAGGGUGCCUCUAGGCCCCACUCUCAGGCUAGGAUGGAGAGGCAGAUCUGGGCCUGGUGAGGUGACCUGCUUCUGGAGGGGCAGGGCCGCACCCGAGAGCAGGGACAGGUGCCCGAACACAGGGUCUCCAGGACGUAGCGCCCCCCCGCAUACUUGAAUGUAUGUGCGUAUUUAUUGCUCACGUCUGUGCCAUGUUGUCAAUGGGUCCUUUCCAACCCAAGAGGUACAUUUGUUUUUCUGUUUUUCCUGAAAAAUAAAGUCGGCCAAGUGAG